AGCCUGGGAAGGAAGAGGGAACGGGUCCUGGCGGUGCUUUGCAAAGGGCCCGUGUUUCUGUUGCGGGAAGCUCCCGGGGGUCGCACGUGCGUCCGAGCCCAAGCCCCUCCCCUCCACUCCCCUUCCUGCGUGCCCCGGAGCCGCCAAGCGGCUACGUUCUUCUCGGCCCGCCGAGAUGGCGCUCGACCCCGCAGUUCUAGUAUGGCUUGAAGGAAAGAAGGUGAAUUUUCCUAUUUUAAGAUGUCUCUUCGUCUACCCUUCCUCAUUUUACUCUGUCGUUAUAGCAAGAAGAGUAAACAGUAGCACCAAACUGUCUUCAGGAGCAAACCAGCAUCUCAGACAUGUCGAAAAAGAUGUUUUGAUCCCUAAAAUAAUGAGAGAAAAGGCCAAAGAGAGGUGUUCUGAACAAGUUCAAGAUUUUACCAAAUGUUGCAAGAACUCUGGAGUUCUUAUGGUAGUAAAAUGCCGGAAAGAAAAUUCUGCAUUGAAAGAAUGUCUAACUGCUUACUAUAAUGAUCCAGCCUUUUAUGAAGAAUGCAAAAUGGAAUACCUGAAGGAAAGGGAAGAAUUCAGAAAAACUGGAAUUCCUACAAAGAAAAGGCUACAGAAGCUUCCAACAAGCAUGUAGGCAGAUACUCAAAUGACAUUCAGGAACUCUAAUAUUCAUGGAAGUCAUUUUAUAGUCCUUAAAUAAUGGACUCAAGCAUAUAUGUUUGCUUUACCUUAAUUAUGGAAAUAUUAACUUUAUCUGAAAUAAAUAUUUUAUUUCAAAGUUUUGGUUUCUUAAAUGGGAAAGGAGUAGUUACUGAAUUGGGAUAUGGUUUUCCUGGUCAUUCUGGACCUUUUGAAAGUUUUCCCACAACUAUAGUUCUAUAACAGUGAUACUGAUUUUUUAGAGUUCAAUAUGGUCCUUAUAUUAUUUUUUUCCAGUGUAUAUGCUAAUGGCUAAUCAUGGGAGCCAAAACUAAAGAAAAGCAGGAAUGGACAACCUUCAAAGGUGUUAAUAAUAACUAGGCAGUAUAGCAGAAUGGCUAUGAACCAGAAUCCUUCCUGAUUCUACCACUUAUUAGCUAUACAGCUGUGGAAGUAAAUCUAAUACAGUUUGUGAGGAUGUACUGAGUAUUGCAUAUAGCAGGUACACGUACAGUGUAUAAGACAGUGCUUCAGACCUGGUACAUGCUCUUAUAUUGGUAGUUACUGUUAGUAGUAGUAGAGGCUUAUUUGGAAACUAUCUUAGUCCAUUUUCUGUUGCUAUGGGAGAAUACCCAAGACCAGGUAAUUUAUAAGAAAAGUUUGUUUGGCUCACAGUUCUGGAGUUUAUUUGCCAGCAGCUUCUGGCAAGGGUUUUCAUACUGCAUCAAAACAUAAUAGGGUGUAAAAAAUAGAAGGACAAACAAGUGUGGGCAAACUUUUAUAACAGCCCGCUCUCUUGAGAACUAAUACCUGUAAUAAUGGCAUAAAUCCAUUCACGAGGGCUCCAGCCUCAUCACCCUAUUACCUCUUAAAGGCUCCAUUUCUUAGUCCUGUUAAAUUAGCAACUAAGUUUCCAACACAUGAACUCUUGGGGGACACAUCAAACCAUAGCAGAACCAUAGAUAAGGAGAUACCUACUUAUAUGAAUUAAUUUUACUUACAUCUUUGAUGUAGAAUUUUCUAAAACAUAAUGUUCUUAACCUGAUAACUUGUUAGUCCUUUAAUCUUUCAUUUUGAAAAGUUAUAUUUCUAAGUGAAUUACCAUUCUGUAACAUAGUAAUGGACUCAGGAAGUAGUAUAAAAAAUUUAUGUCCCAAUUUAAUAAUUUGAGCUUUUAUAUUAAAAGUUAUUUUUUCCCCAUGAGCUGUUAACUCUUCCACAGCCAUUGUAACUAGUUUCAAGAUAAGUAAAUUUUACGUAUAUUUUCACAGUCCUCAUUAAAAUCACAAAUAGAAAUUACUACCCACUAAGACAAGGUUUAACUUUCCCUAAUCCCAUGCAAUAGAUCUGAGAGAUUUUUUUUUAAGAAAGAAUUUAAAUAGGACACUAAAGAAUCAAUUCAAGUUCCACACUUUACUCUUGAGUGAACCACUCAAAAAACUAUUUUACUUUUAUUUGAAAUACAAAGAAACCACAUUUUCCCAGGCCACAGAUCAAAAGGAGGGAGAUUACUAGAGCAGACAAAAGCAAAGCAAAUAUAGAAAUCUAGAGACCACACAGCAUAGGGGCAAACAUGCCCAUAUUUCCACAUUGACCUUUGGUAUUGGUGCAUUUCCUAGAGCACAGGAAGUUAACUGUUUUUAGAGAUAAAUGAAAAUGGAAGAGUUACUUUAAGAAGCUAGUGAAAUAUACAAUCUAUUUUAUAGCUUUGAUUAAAAUCAGAAGUAGCCCACUUCAUGUAGAAAAUUCACUUAUGUACAUGUUGCUUUCCCCAUAGAAGCCAGAUUAGAUUACACAGUAUAAAUAAUAUGUUCAUCCUCCUUAUGUCAAAGACUAAACCAUUCAUUGUAGCCUUCAGAAUACCCAUGUGUAUCCAUACUGAAGAUUUUUUUCACCUGGUACAUCUGUCUCAGUUGUGUCUUGCUUGCUUAUGGGUGCCUCUGUUGAUAUUAUUCCCUGUUAAUAUGUGGUAACCCACAGGUUUUUUACCCCUUAAGAUACACCUUCUCCAAGUAGCCUUUCUGAAUUAAGAUCAGUACUUUGUUGUCACAUGAUUCAGCUCUUCAAGUCUGAAUUUUCCCAUUUAUUUUGGUUUUCUAAUGUUUCACAUAGGCAUGUUCCUGCUUUUAAGAAUUCAGUUCCAUUUUGGCAGCAACUCAGUAAGUCUUACAGAUGUAAAUUUUACUUUAGCUAAUAAGGGAGCAAGAGGAAGGAAUAGGUGGCUUUUUGUUAUGUUUUCUUCAUUCUGUCGAUUUAUGGAUGUACUGAAUUGAACCUUAUAAAAAGAAAUCUAAAGAUUCCAAAGGAAGCUCUUUAGAGCAAGUUUCAGCUAGUAUGAAAGAAGUCAACAUAAAAUAUUCAAUUUUAAAUAGAUUCAUAAGCUACAGAUGGGCCACUGUUUUUUGGUUGUUUGAAUUUUACCUAGAACAGAGAUAUCAAGUGUAGAUUUAAAAGCUUCUAGCUGGGUAAAAAAUUUUUGGCUAAUCUUUCCUUACUAAAGAACCUUAUACAUCAUUUGUCUAACACUUUAAACUGUCACAGUCACUGACUUUUUAGUAUACCUGUUUGAUAGCUAUCAUCACUGUACUGUUUAAAUGGAAAAUAAUUUUCUCCACUCAAAAGCUGGUUUAACAAAUGUCUAUUGUAUGAAUCAUAUUAACAACCAACAAUUAGUACUAGAUUUUGAGAUCUAUAGGCAAGGACAAUAUUUCACAUCCACUUCAAUUUCAAACAAAAAUAUUUAUUUUAAUUAAACAAUUUCUUGGUAUUGUUCAAAACAUUAAUCAAGCAAUUAUCUCAUAAGACUUUUUUUCUUUACAAAGGAAAAUUUCCAAUUUUGGUUUUAAAAAAGGCAAACCAGUAAGCUACAUUAGAGAUCAGAUAUAAUAUACAGCCUAUGCAGCCACAUGAGAAAUAGUUUUUGCUGCUUUGUUAUUACACAGGUAGUUGCUUCCUUCAGCUAAAGCCUGGAGUAUUGUAUUUCUUUUAUGCAUAUUGGGUUUGGUUCUAUUACUUGGCAGGAGAUUGUACUCCCCUGAGUCAGCUGUGUUCAUUGGUCAGAAUAAAUUCCAGCAUCUGACACCAAUUCCAUUAAUCACAGACAAGCUUGAAUAAGUGUAAGAUAAUAGAAAAAAAUAUCUAGUGAAUGGCGAACAUUGUCUAUGUAUGUAUGCUAUUCAGUAAUACAGUAGAAGAGAUCUGAGAUAUUGAGUUCAAGAUAUAUGAAACUGUCUAUCAAAAAGGAUAAAAGUCCUCCUACAUGAAAUACUUUAAUUCAGGCAAAAGGUGUAUGAACCAAGUAAAUCUCCACCCUGAAAGAACUUAAAUUUCCAUGUGAAGCCAUCUUUAUUUCCUUCUUUAUUUCCAAAUAAUUGGCCACUUAGAAUAAGUGUGGACAUUUCAUGAUCGACAAUAUCAAUACAGCCCAAACCCUGAUUUCUAUGAUUAAAAAUAAUAAUUUUAAAUCACUUUCUCAAUAAAUAGAAUAUUACAUUUCAACACAAAGUCUAACAAUUUAGAAGCUGCUCUACACAAUGUGCAGCUAGCUGUAGUCUCUUUGAAGAAAAUGACUUUUUAUCAUUACACACAUUUAUGUUUAUAUUAUGGCCCACAGAAGGGCAGAUUAGACUGAAAUCUGUGUGAUGCUCCUUCUACUACUUAUUGAAUAGUGUGUAGGGUUACAAUCAUUUGUUUACACCCCAGAGUUUUUCAACUAUUUCAUUUUUUUUUUUUUUUUUCCCAAUUAGGACUUAAGGAAUGUGCUGGGACAAAGUUGGCUUCAGUGAUCAGGUUGUUUCAAGUCUUAGAAUUCAAACUUCAAUUCUAAAAAAAUUUUAUCAACAAAACACUGUGACCAAAAAAUCACUUUAAAUCUUAAAUAUUGAAACGCAAUAGCAUAUAAAGAUGGUAUAACCUAAGAUGCUUUUAUUUCAUUAUAUUUUCAAUAUCUUUACGCAUUAUAACAACAGAAAUGUAACCUACUCACAUUGCCAUUUGUUCCAUUAUGCAAUUUGAAGAAACAUGUUUUCCUUUUAUUUUUAUGAACAGAUAUUUAGACAUUUCACAUUUUGUAAAACCACGUCUACAAUCUCCAAUUCCAUUCUUCUGAGAGGCAAAAUUUUACAAUUAAUAUAGAAGGCAGAGUUUUUUAAACACCUUAAGUUUACUUAUUAAUUAGUAUAGUAGCAUAUUUCAGAUUCUUAGAAUAUGGAGCUAGAGGGUGCUCUUUCAUACUAGAAAACCAACUAUGUUGGUUUUUGUACUAUUGUACAGUGUGUUCAAAUAUAGAUACUGAAGACCUCUGCAAAAUUUUAAUCAAAAUCUCCUUUCAGUUUGUUAAAUAAUUUCUUGGGAGGACCACUGAAAGAGAUAAGUGUCCUCAUGGUGAAAUCGUGAAUCUCUUCCAAAUUAAUUCUUAUAAAGGCAGUUCUGAUUAUGUUGAUCCAAGUAAUGCAGUGGUGGAAGGUUGGGUAAAGGCAAAGUUUUAGUUUUAGUUUCCCCAAAUGCUGUCUCACUUGAUUUAGGAGGACUUGGAAAUACCCAGGAAUUGUCUUCCAGAGAAUUUCUGCCAUAAGAACUGUGUUCCUGAAAGCAUGUACCAUCAUUAGGAAUGGAUCUCUCAUUGUCUGUCCAUGAUUGGAGGAUUGCUUUCUCUGAUAAAACCUUUACAUCUCCUGGUAAAGGGGAAGAUGUGGUAUGACAAAGAGCUUUGCCAUUUGGUAAGAGAGGGGGAUGUCUUGUGUAUGUUGCAGUAAAAUUCAUCAAGUGCAGUUUUGUGCUGUCUCUUCCAAGGUCUUCACUGCAUCCUACAGGGGCACAGGCUAAAAAGAAAACACAGACUAAAUGUCAGUUUUCAUUACAUUUGUGAUCAUAAAAUUCGAUAACACUUCACCAAUUUGAAUUCUAGAACUGGUGAUGAAAUUAAGAUUUCCAAGUUAGUGUGAUCAUUGAGGCACUGUGACUAGGAGAUAAAUGACAGAUGAUCUGAGUUUUAAUCCUGGAUCAGCAAUUUACUGUGACUUUAGAUAUUUGUCUCUUAGCUGCUCCUGAUGUCUCUUUCCUUGUCUGCAGAAUGGAUAUAGAAUUCCUGUCCCAACUAUGUCAUAGAGCUUUUAAAAGAUGAAGAACUACAUAUUUUUAAAAGUUGGAAACUAAUACAGUUAAAAUACAAAUAAAGAUCCUGUUCUUGGCUCUUAUUGUGGCUGGAGAAGGAUUGCAGACUGUUCACAUGUCAGUGGGGACUGAGACAGUUCUUAAGUUUUAGCAUUUUUUAGUUAAAUAUAAUAUUCCUUUGCUCAAACUCUUUGUCCACAGGCAGUCCAAAAGCAAAUUUUUUAGAAAUAAUUGCAUUUUUAAUUGGUGAGACCCAAAUGAAGUUUUUAUAUAUCAAAGGCUUUUAUGGAUAAAGCAGUUUAAAUAAAAUUUGUGAAAUCUUGUUUCUUGUAAAACACAGCAAAUGUUAAUGCUACUGUGGUCACAAUGUAGGUAAAGUAAAAAAAAAAAAAAAAA